AAAAGGAGGCGCCUGCUGGCCUCCCCUUACAGUGCUUGUUCGGGGCGCUCCGCUGGCUUCUUGGACAAUUGCGCCAUGUGUGCUGCUCGGCUAGCGGCGGCGGCGGCGGCGGCCCAGUCGGUGUAUGCCUUCUCGGCGCGCCCGCUGGCCGGCGGGGAGCCUGUGAGCCUGGGCUCCCUGCGGGGCAAGGUACUACUUAUCGAGAAUGUGGCGUCCCUCUGAGGCACCACGGUCCGGGACUACACCCAGAUGAACGAGCUGCAGCGGCGCCUCGGACCCCGGGGCCUGGUGGUGCUCGGCUUCCCGUGCAACCAGUUUGGGCAUCAGGUGCGCCGGGCGGAGCGGGGCGGGGCGGGGGCGGACGUGCAGUAGUGGCUGGGGGCGCCGGCGGUGUGCUGGUGGGUGCCGUCGGCUCCAUGCGCGGAGAGUCUGGCUACUCUCUCGUUUCCUUUCUGUUGCUCGUAGCUGCUGAAAUUCCUCUCCGCCCUUGGGAUUGCGCAUGGAGGGCAAAAUCCCGGUGACUCAUAGAAAAUCUCCCUUGUUUGUGGUUAGAACGUUUCUCUCCUCCUCUUGACCCCGGGUUCUAGCUGCCCUUCUCUCCUGUAGGAGAACGCCAAGAACGAAGAGAUUCUGAAUUCCCUCAAGUACGUCCGGCCUGGUGGUGGGUUCGAGCCCAACUUCAUGCUCUUCGAGAAGUGCGAGGUGAACGGUGCGGGGGCGCACCCUCUCUUCGCCUUCCUGCGGGAGGCCCUGCCAGCUCCCAGCGACGACGCCACCGCGCUUAUGACCGACCCCAAGCUCAUCACCUGGUCUCCGGUGUGUCGCAACGAUGUUGCCUGGAACUUUGAGAAGUUCCUGGUGGGCCCUGACGGUGUGCCCCUACGCAGGUACAGCCGCCGCUUCCAGACCAUUGACAUCGAGCCUGACAUCGAAGCCCUGCUGUCUCAAGGGCCCAGCUGUGCCUAGGGCGCCCCUCCUACCCCGGCUGCUUGGCAGUUGCAGUGCUGCUGUCUCGGGGGGGUUUUCAUCUAUGAGGGUGUUUCCUCUAAACCUACGAGGGAGGAACACCUGAUCUUACAGAAAAUACCACCUCGAGAUGGGUGCUGGUCCUGUUGAUCCCAGUCUCUGCCAGACCAAGGCGAGUUUCCCCACUAAUAAAGUGCCGGGUGUCAGCAGAA